ACCUUGACUCCAGGAGCUGCAGCAGAGCAGGUAACAGCUCUUGCACCUGUUUCUCUUGCACCUGACGUGCAGCUGCUCCUACCCACCUCUCCUGGCUGAGCCUUGCCUGAUACAGCAGCCCGGAGGCACCACUUGCUUCCCGAGUCUCACCCUCCCAGGCAGCUCCUACACUCAACUGCUUCUCUAGGAAAGGUCUCACCUCCAGCCUGGAGCAGUCGGGAUUACAGUCAAUGGUUAACUUGACCCAGCUCAGGAGGGGCCUGGCUCAGUCUGGGCAAAGCCCUUCAGAGCAGCUCACAGAACCCAGCUGCAGAAAGCCCCAUCCUUGGCUUAGGGAGCGCCAUGACGACUGAAAUUGGUUGGUGGAAGCUGACUUUCCUCCGGAAAAAGAAAUCCACUCCCAAAGUGCUGUAUGAGAUCCCUGACACCUAUGCCCAAACAGAGGGAGAUGCAGAACCCCCGAGGCCUGACGCUGGAGGCCCCAACAGCGACUUUAACACCCGCCUGGAGAAGAUUGUGGACAAGAGCACAAAGGGCAAGCACGUCAAGGUCUCCAACUCAGGACGCUUCAAGGAGAAGAAGAAAGUGAGAGCCACGCUGGCAGAGAACCCUAACCUCUUUGAUGAUCACGAGGAAGGACGGUCAUCAAAGUGAAGGGCUGAGGAGGGUGCUAGCACCUCUUGGCUCCCUGCCAUCAGCCAGAUCUGAGACAGGACCUUGCCACGCUGGCCUCUUUGGCCAUAGCUGAAGCUGUGGGGCCAGUUGAUACCUGCUGGCAGGAAAUGGCUGUUUUUUAGGUUUGUAUUUAUGUGCCGCCACUUUUGUAAGGCCUGGGAGAUCCCAGGGUCCUCCACCCUCCCCCUGACCACAUACAAAGGCACUCUAGUUCAAGAGUGAAAAGUCUCACCCAGGAGGAACAGCCCUCCUUGAAGCAAUGGCAGGGCCAGCAGGGAGGUGGGCAUGGCAGGGAAUGGAGAGAGUGAGCCAGACAGACUUCACCUCCUUACUGGACACAGGGUCAAGGGCGAGUUUCAAUUGCUGCUCCCUUUACUUUCUCUACCUGUGACUACUCCCUGGACCAAUCCUGAGGAGGGCACAUUUUCCAGAAGCCACGUGAUAGGGGCUGGUUUCUGUGGAGCCAGAGGCAGAGACACUGAACUUGAGCUCACCUCCUAACACCGGCAGUAAACUUCCUGGAACUUUGCCCUCAGGUGCGGAGGGGACAGAGGACCCUGGCACUCUGUUAGGGUGCUGUAGAAGACUAGAUUGAUGGUAGUUUGGCCUGUUAGUUCCUGUUUUGGCCAUGACUUUUGCAGAUGGCAAGUCACACACCCUCAAAGGGAAGCUACACGGGCCAAAUCGGGGGAGUGGGUGGGGAAUUUUCUCCUCUCCCUUUCCUACUAUAAUAGUAUUUAAGACAUAUCAGCUCCAGAGAUGAGUCCUGGAGCCUUGAAUUUUGUUUAACAAAAUAAUUGUAGGUUUCUCUCUGUAAUAACAACGCUGGAAAGGCAGAGAACCUCUUUUAUGCUCAUGUCUUGCAUUUAUUGAGAUGACUGUUUCUCAUGCCUUUAUGUUCCUUCAUGUAAGUAAAGUGGACCUUUGUGCUCAAA